GGGCAGCGACUGUCAUGGCGGCGGCCGCCCCCAAUGCCGGAGGCUCGGCCCCUGAGACAGCGGGUUCCGCCGAAGCUCCGCUGCAGUACAGCCUGCUCCUGCAGUACCUGGUGGGUGACAAGCGUCAGCCCCGGCUCCUGGAGCCUGGGAGCCUGGGCGGGAUCCCAAGUCCAGCCAAGAGUGAGGAGCAGAAGAUGAUCGAGAAGGCGAUGGAAAGCUGCGCUUUCAAGGCUGCGCUGGCCUGCGUGGGAGGAUUUGUCUUAGGAGGUGCAUUUGGGGUGUUUACCGCUGGCAUCGAUACCAACGUGGGCUUUGACCCUAAGGAUCCUUACCGUACACCGACUGCAAAAGAAGUGCUGAAAGACAUGGGGCAGAGAGGAAUGUCCUAUGCCAAAAAUUUCGCCAUUGUGGGAGCCAUGUUUUCUUGUACUGAGUGUUUGAUAGAAUCUUACCGGGGAACAUCAGACUGGAAGAACAGUGUCAUCAGUGGCUGCAUCACGGGAGGAGCUAUUGGUUUCAGAGCUGGCUUAAAGGCUGGGGCCAUUGGUUGUGGAGGUUUUGCUGCUUUCUCUGCUGCGAUUGAUUAUUACCUCCGGUGAGAGUAAUUGCCUGCAGGGAAGGAUGAUGCCAGCCCCGGAUCCGGGCUGCUCUCUGGAGGACAGUUUCUGUACCACACCAGGGCCUUGCUUCAGGGCCUGAAGACAUUCAUUUUCCCUCAUGUCGUUGGUAUUCUGAGGGAGCUGCCUGGCUUCUCUGCCUCCAGCCUUUGGGGUAGCCACACUUUGCUGCUCCUGGACUCCAGCCAGCCUUCACAGAGGACGUCCCGUGCCAGAUUCUCUCACAGCAGAUCGGGAGACAGGAUGUUGACAUAUAGGAAUUCAGCUCCACAAAGCUUCAGGCCUGACCACAGCUGGCCCUCUAGGUUGUUUGGUGUUGUGGGCACAGAGGUGACAGUGUCUCUGCAGGCACUCAGGAAGCUGUUCUACCUUGGAACUCCAUGCAACUAUCCGUCUCGAAUACCAGGGCAGGGCAAGGCGGACUGAUGCCGUCCAACCAAUUAUCUCACUUGUUUUGUGUUCUGUCAUCCUUGUUUUUUUUUUAAAAAUACACUCCCCUCCCCCACCGCCACACACCUUACAGUUCAAAAGGUUGGUUUAUUUGUAUUUUAUUUUCAAAUUCCCUAUUCCAAAAAUAGUGCCGGGUGGCCCAAAGAUAACAUCUGAAGGGAAAGAAUGAGAAAGCUCCCAGGGAAGCGGGGGAUGGGGCGCUGAGGCAGGGUUGUUAGAGGACUGUGUCAUCCUCACCAAGCUCAUUACAUCUGCCAGGGCCUGCCUCAAGAAGCCCAGCCCAGCCUUUUCCUGGGAUGCAGUGAAAUCCCAUCCAUGAACUCGAUGGGCCCCUCCUGUGCCGGCCGAGAGGCACACACUGCCUUCACGACGUGACUGCUGGACCUGGCCGAGCUUGAGGCCACAUGUGAAGGGUCCUGCUGUGGUCAUCUUGGUGACUCGGUCACAGCAGCUACUGGCCAAGAUCAGACGUCGCUGAGGGGCUGUUCACCACCAUCCUCGUUCUCCAGGGUCAAGGAAGUGUUUUAACAUGUCGUGUUUUCGACUUGACCUUGUGGUAUUUUUCUUGGCCUAGUUGUGUGCCAUGGAUAUUAAAAAAAAAAAAAAAAAAAUCCGUCUACAGUUGGGCUUCAGCACUGGUGCUGCUUUACCCUGGUGCUCUGUGGGGGGAUGACACUGCUGGAGUCAGGCCUUUGCUCUUGGGUGGGGCACAGGCAGGUCGCUUGGUGGGGGCCACACAGUGCUGGGCACCUUCAGCCAGUGGUGAUGAGUCUCCUUUUUCCUAUAAUACGGUAAUUCCUCUAUCCUUUCCUUUUUUGCCUUCUUCCUCAUCUGCCCUGUCUUCUGGCCCACACACUCUUAACCAGCGUUCACACUCAGUGUACAUGGCCUGGAGGCCCGAGUGUUUGUACAUGAGUGAUGAUGUCAAACCCAGCUGGUAACACCUUCCUUGGGUCAUGUUUGCCAUUUUCUUGGAAUGAAUGUGAGUUCCUGCUCAGGGCUCAUGUCCUUUUACAGUGAAUUCUAUAUAACGCCCCUCCCAGUCUCACAGCUAGGAGGCUUCAUCACUGCUAGGCCAGUUGGAGCGUUCCCUAGAGCUCAGAACAAAUUGUUUCCUCUGCUGUCCCUAAAUAUAGGACACCUACAAGCACUCUGAAGCAAGGGCAGACAUUCCCACCUGGUACCUGUCAAAGUCCUAGGAUGCCUGGGAUCUUCCAUCUUUCAGUCUAGCACGUGGGACCAAAUACAAGAGAUGCUGCCCUCACAACAGCCUUGGAAAAGAUGAGCGCCAGGGCUGUCAGUACCCAUCGGUUCAGUAAGCGAGGCAUUGUCCACGCUGCCUAUUCACUCGAGAGAUGAAUAGUUUCCUGUUUUCGAUGGCUGGGGAGCCAGUAUGAGCUCAUAAACCAAACAGCAAUUUUCAGAGACAUCUGUUCCUGAUCUUCAGAAUAAACUCAGUGUCCAGUUGCUUCGGCUGGUGGGAGCCAAUAUUCACGCCACUGACUCUCUCAAAGGGAGGGUGGGCCCUCGGAGACCCAGCUUCUCUGACAAGCAGAUUAGACCAAAAGGCUGCCUCAAAGAUAUGCCACUUUGAAGGAAAGCGUAGAGAAGCGUUUACAUAAAAGAAGACGCUUCCUGUUCAGUGGACAACUUCAUGCCACUUUCAAGGCACACCGAUGGCCAGGUGGGACAUUUGUACUGUAGCAGCACAUGGCAAAGGUGAGCCAGAAGCAGCCUGGAUGCUGGCUGAUCCGGAGGCCUUUGUGAAGAGCAAGGAGAGGGCUCCAGCCCACCUCCCCGCAGCUCUGCCCCAGCCCCCGUGGGCCACAGGGAGGCUCAAGGGGAGUGAACUAGGUAAACAGAUUCCUGGAAACUCACAUCUGGAUGCAGCUGGAAGAGUUAAAUAUUUACAUUGGUGGCUUCCCUGGACCACCGCGAACACAAACAUCCACACCACAGGGCUGAGUUUUGUGCAAAUGAUGGGGCUUUGCAUUUUUUAUUAACAUUUUCCUCUCACGUGGUUUACAUCAAUUUAUAAUAAUCUACAUAAGUUGAAACAGAACAUAGACAAAAAAAUAUAUCCUUACCAACUUAUUAAAGUCAGAUAUUCAUGAA